GGAUUGAGCUGACCACAGGCCACACCAGACUCCUCUCUGCUCCUGAGGAAGACAGGGCAGCCCGGCGCCACCCGCUCGGCCCUCACGAAGCUAACACAGAGGAUAGACAAGCUCCCUCGGGCCUUUGCAACAUCACUGCCAGGAAGGAAAGAGUCAAAAGAUGCUCCCUGGAGCCUGGCUGCUCUGGACCUCCCUCCUGCUCCUGGCCAGGCCUGCCCAGCCCUGUCCCAUGGGUUGUGACUGCUUCGUCCAGGAGGUGUUCUGCUCAGAUGAGGAGCUUGCCACCGUCCCACUGGACAUCCCGCCAUAUACGAAAAACAUCAUCUUUGUGGAGACCUCGUUCACCACAUUGGAAACCAGAGCUUUUGGCAGUAACCCCAACUUGACCAAGGUGGUCUUCCUCAACACUCAGCUCUGCCAGUUUAGGCCGGAUGCCUUCGGGGGGCUGCCCAGGCUGGAGGACCUGGAGGUCACAGGCAGUAGCUUCUUGAACCUCAGCACCAACAUCUUCUCCAACCUGACCUCGCUGGGCAAGCUCACCCUCAACUUCAACAUGCUGGAGGCUCUGCCCGAGGGUCUUUUCCAGCACCUGGCUGCCCUGGAGUCCCUCCACCUGCAGGGGAACCAGCUCCAGGCCCUGCCCAGGAGGCUCUUCCAGCCUCUGACCCAUCUGAAGACACUCAACCUGGCCCAGAACCUCCUGGCCCAGCUCCCGGAGGAGCUGUUCCACCCACUCACCAGCCUGCAGACCCUGAAGCUGAGCAACAACGCGCUCUCUGGUCUCCCCCAGGGUGUGUUUGGCAAACUGGGCAGCCUGCAGGAGCUCUUCCUGGACAGCAACAACAUCUCGGAGCUGCCCCCUCAGGUGUUCUCCCAGCUCUUCUGCCUAGAGAGGCUGUGGCUGCAACGCAACGCCAUCACGCACCUGCCGCUCUCCAUCUUUGCCUCCCUGGGUAAUCUGACCUUUCUGAGCUUGCAGUGGAACAUGCUUCGGGUCCUGCCUGCCGGCCUCUUUGCCCACACCCCGUGCCUGGUUGGCCUGUCUCUGACCCAUAACCAGCUGGAGACUGUCGCUGAGGGCACCUUUGCCCACCUGUCCAACCUGCGUUCCCUCAUGCUCUCAUACAAUGCCAUUACCCACCUCCCAGCUGGCAUCUUCAGAGACCUGGAGGAGUUGGUCAAACUCUACCUGGGCAGCAACAACCUUACGGCGCUGCACCCAGCCCUCUUCCAGAACCUGUCCAAGCUGGAGCUGCUCAGCCUCUCCAAGAACCAGCUGACCACACUUCCGGAGGGCAUCUUCGACACCAACUACAACCUGUUCAACCUGGCCCUGCACGGUAACCCCUGGCAGUGCGACUGCCACCUGGCCUACCUCUUCAACUGGCUGCAGCAGUACACCGAUCGGCUCCUGAACAUCCAGACCUACUGCGCUGGCCCUGCCUACCUCAAAGGCCAGGUGGUGCCCGCCUUGAAUGAGAAGCAGCUGGUGUGUCCCGUCACCCGGGACCACUUGGGCUUCCAGGUCACGUGGCCGGACGAAAGCAAGGCAGGGGGCAGCUGGGAUCUGGCUGUGCAGGAAAGGGCAGCCCGGAGCCAGUGCACCUACAGCAACCCCGAGGGCACCGUGGUGCUCGCCUGUGACCAGGCCCAGUGUCGCUGGCUGAACGUCCAGCUCUCUCCUCAGCAGGGCUCCCUGGGACUGCAGUACAAUGCUAGUCAGGAGUGGGACCUGAGGUCGAGCUGCGGUUCUCUGCGGCUCACCGUGUCUAUCGAGGCUCGGGCAGCAGGGCCCUAGUAGCAGCGCAUACAGGAGCUGGGGAAGGGGGCCUCUGGGGCCUGACCAGGCGACAGGUAGGGGCGGAGGGGAGCUGAGUCUCCGAAGCCUUGGCUUUUCACAUGCAAGGGACAGGGUUACAUCCCCAAGGUGAGGGGGUGGAGUCUGGUCUGCUCCACUAACCAGGGUCUCCUCCUCCUCUUCCUUCAUCGCUUCUCCUGGAGUGUGCGGCCUAACAAGGCCAUCCUUAUGCCUUGCAAAGCACCCUCAAAAGCUGCACCACAGCCUGGAGAAUAAAAUAUCCUCAGCCCUGAUGCCUCCCCAUUAUGUAACACCCAACCGCUCUCACCUACACCCUGAGGUCUAUUCACUGCAUCCCAGUGAUACAAAGUGGAGGCCACUGCCUUCUGACAUCUGGCUCAAAAGCCCAGUGUCUGUUUCCAUUUAUUUCCCUGGAAUUUCAUUUAAAAUUGGUAUAGAGAAAAAAAGGAUGUGACAGAAGCAGAGAUGACCAGAAAGCACAGGGGCAGGGUUCUGACUGGCGUGUGGGAGACCCUGUGGCCGGCACCCACCUCCACACGAGGACUAAGCUCUGAUUUUUUUAUCUUGCCCAAAUUCCUACCUAAGGGGUCUAGGGAGUCGCGCCUUACAAAUCAUAAAUUCUCAUCAGAUGGGUUUUAUUUGACCCUGUAUAUCAUGACUUAUUUUUAAUCUGACUAUGGCAUAACAUUACAAGACGAGGCAAAAAUAUUUAACCCCCAAAUAUAUUUCCUUGCCCUACCUUGAACUUGCCCUGCAGAGUCUCUUGUGAGGAGAAUCCACAUCCUAUAAAGAAGCCCCUUUCCCCUUUGUUUUCCUUCCUUUCUUUCCAGUCCAGGAGAUCAUCAACUAAGAGCCAGGCACCCCUUUUAAGUCGAUAAGAAACAGUUUACAACCUGCUCUCUCUCUCUCUGAAGUCUGCUGAGAGCUUCCCCUGCACAAUAAAACUUGGCCUCCACGAUCCUUUAUCUUAACCUGAACAUUCCUUUCCAUUGAUCCCAGGUCUUCAGCUAAGCUCAACCAAUUGUCAACCAGAAAAUGUUUAAAUUUACCUACAGCCUGGAAGCACCCACCCCCGCUGCUUCGAGUUGUCCUGCCUUUCUGAACUCAACCAAUGUAUUUCUUAAAUGUAUUUGAUUGAUGCCUCAUUCCUCCCUAAAAUGUAUAAAACCAAGCUGUACCUCGACCACCUUGGGCACAUGUUCCCAGGCCCUCCUGAGGUCUGUGUCACGGGCCAUGGCCACUCAUAUUUGGCUCAGAAUAAAUCUCUUCAAAUAUU